AGUGUUUGUGUUGGAAGCUCAGCUGAUGCAGGCCGGUUGGAGUGGACGUCAUUGCCGGGAACGAGCGAGUCGCCGCUGCAGCCCUAGUGACUGCGGCCUGCAUCCCGAUUGUCUUCUCCUCCAAGGUCUACAUGAUUACCUGAAGUUUAAUAAUUUUGCCUUUCUAGAGUGUUAUACAGCUGGAAUCAUACUGCUAUGGUCCGAAUGUUUGUGCCUCUCAAAAUUCAUGUGGAAAUCAUAACCGCUAAAGUGAUGGUAUUAAGAGGUAAGACCAUGAAUUAUGGCAUUUCUUAAAUGAAGCGUUCAAGAAGUGAGAGAAUGUCAUAGAAAAUAAAUGAUUUUUAAGUUAUGUCUAUUAAUCUGACUGUAGAUAUAUAUAUUUACCUCCUUAGUAAUGCAAGAAGUGUUUGUGGGAAGCAGAGAAGCAAGCAACUGUAUUUCUUGUUCUCACCUAAGCAUUACUGGAGGAUAAGCCACAUCAGUCUACAAAGAGGUUUUCAUACAAACAUAAUAAGAUGUAAAUGGACCAAAAGUGAAGCACAUUCUUGCAGUAAGCACUGUUACUCUCCAAGCAACCAUGGUUUACAUAUUGGGAUUUUGAAACUUAGCACUUCUGCUCCCAAGGGACUUACAAAAGUGAACAUUUGUAUGUCCCGUAUUAAAAGUACUUUGAACUCUGUUUCAAAGGCUGUUUUUGGCAAUCAAAAUGAAAUGAUUUCACGUUUAGCUCAAUUUAAGCCAAGUUCCCAAAUUUUAAGAAAAGUAUCGGAUAGUGGCUGGUUAAAACAGAAAAACAUCAAACAAGCCAUCAAAUCUCUGAAAAAAUAUAGUGACAAAUCAGCAGAAAAGAGUCCUUUUCCAGAAGAGAAAAGUCACAUUAUAGACAAAGAAGAAGAUAUAGGUAAACGCAGUCUUUUUCAUUACACAAGUUCUAUAACCACAAAAUUUGGAGACUCAUUCUACUUUUUAUCAAAUCAUAUUAAUUCAUAUUUCAAACGUAAGGAAAAAAUGUCUCAACAAAAGGAAAAUGAACAUUUCCGGGACAAAUCAGAACUUGAAGAUAAAAAGGUAGAAGAGGGGAAAUUAAGAUCUCCAGAUCCUGGCAUCCUGGCUUAUAAGCCAGGCUCAGAAUCUGUACAUACGGUGGACAAGCCUACAAGUCCUUCUGCGAUACCUGAUGUUCUUCAAGUUUCAACUAAACAAAGUAUUGCUAACUUUCUUUCUCGUCCCACGGAAGGUGUACAAGCUUUAGUAGGUGGUUAUAUUGGUGGACUUGUCCCCAAAUUAAAGUAUGAUUCAAAGAGUCAGUCAGAAGAACAGGAAGAGCCUGCUAAAACUGAUCAGGCUGUCAGCAAAGACAGAAAUGCAGAGGAGAAAAAGCGUUUAUCUCUUCAGCGAGAAAAGAUUAUCGCAAGGGUGAGUAUUGAUAACAGGACCCGGGCAUUAGUUCAGGCAUUAAGAAGAACAACUGACCCAAAGCUCUGCAUUACUAGGGUUGAAGAACUGACUUUUCAUCUUCUAGAAUUUCCUGAAGGAAAAGGAGUGGCUGUCAAGGAAAGAAUUAUUCCAUAUUUAUUACGACUGAGACAAAUUAAGGAUGAAACUCUUCAGGCUGCAGUUAGAGAAAUUUUGGCCCUAAUUGGCUAUGUGGAUCCAGUGAAAGGGAGAGGAAUCCGAAUUCUCUCAAUUGAUGGUGGAGGAACAAGGGGCGUGGUUGCUCUCCAGACCCUACGAAAAUUAGUUGAACUUACUCAGAAGCCAGUUCAUCAGCUCUUUGAUUACAUUUGUGGUGUAAGCACAGGUGCCAUAUUAGCUUUCAUGUUGGGGUUGUUUCAUAUGCCCUUGGAUGAAUGUGAGGAACUUUAUCGAAAAUUAGGAUCAGAUGUAUUUUCACAAAAUGUCAUUGUUGGAACAGUAAAAAUGAGUUGGAGCCAUGCAUUUUAUGACAGUCAAACAUGGGAAAACAUUCUUAAGGAUAGGAUGGGAUCUGCACUGAUGAUUGAAACAGCAAGAAACCCCACAUGUCCUAAGGUAGCUGCUGUAAGUACCAUAGUAAAUAGAGGGAUAACACCCAAAGCUUUUGUGUUCAGAAACUAUGGUCAUUUUCCUGGAAUCAACUCUCAUUAUUUGGGAGGCUGUCAGUAUAAAAUGUGGCAGGCCAUUAGAGCCUCAUCUGCUGCUCCAGGCUACUUUGCAGAAUAUGCAUUGGGAAAUGAUCUUCAUCAAGAUGGAGGUUUGCUUCUGAAUAACCCUUCGGCAUUAGCUAUGCAUGAGUGUAAAUGUCUUUGGCCAGAUGUGCCGUUAGAGUGCAUAGUAUCCCUGGGCACUGGACGUUAUGAGAGUGAUGUGAGAAACACGGUAACAUACACAAGCUUGAAAACUAAACUUUCUAAUGUUAUCAACAGUGCUACAGAUACAGAAGAAGUCCAUAUAAUGCUUGAUGGCCUGUUACCUCCUGACACCUAUUUUAGAUUCAAUCCUGUAAUGUGUGAAAACAUACCUCUAGAUGAAAGUCGAAAUGAAAAGCUGGAUCAGCUGCAGUUGGAAGGGUUGAAAUACAUAGAAAGAAAUGAACAAAAAAUGAAAAAAGUUGCAAAAAUAUUAAGUCAAGAAAAAACAACUCUGCAGAAAAUUAAUGAUUGGAUAAAAUUAAAAACUGAUAUGUAUGAAGGACUUCCAUUCUUUUCAAAAUUGUGAUGAGUAUAUGCUUAUGUUCUCAUAAAUGAAGGUCUGUUUAGAAGAUCAACCACAUUCAAUAAGGAAUUGUGGGGUUCGACAUGAGUUAACUUUGAAAUACGUAUGAAUUCUGGAGAAUCCUGAAAAAGACGGUGCUUCAACCAGCUUGCAUAGCACAGAGAAUAUUCUUGGUUACAGAAUUCAUAUGGGAACUAGGCUUUUAAGAUGUUAAUAAUUAGCUAAGCUUUAGUAACCCUUACUGUGCUAGUAGAUUUUAGUAGAUAUUGGUGUUAUAUUGUUUGAUGUUUGAAAAUAUAUUAAUAUAUGUGCCGAACAAGAAACCGAAAGCUAUAUUGUACUGUGUAUUUUUACUUUAGUCCUCAUAAUCAUGUUGAAUUUAUGUGAUCAUUGAUUUUAUUUCAUAUGGAAAAGCUAAUUUCUUCUUAAAUUUACAUUACCUAAUAUUCUCACUAGCUAUGUUCUCCAAUCCACACUGCCUUUUAUUGUAAUAUCAUCUAAAUAGAUGCAGAAAAAUGGAAUUUUCUCUAUUAAAGUAUUUUACAUUUGACAUAAAAAAGAACCAGAUACAGUUUUCUAUUCAGAUAUGUUUAUUUUAACAUUGUUUGGUUAAAAAAGGUGAAGUUCCAGUCAACCACUUUUUACCCCUGAAAUUUCAAGAUAAUGCUAUAUUAACUUUUCCAGAUCUAACACUAGCUUAUUCUUCCCUGUUAUAAAAUGGUUUGAACUUACUGAGGAGAUAUUCCUAUCAUUAACAAAAAUAAACUAUUUAAAUAAUCUGUUGUUAAAAGGCUAAUGUCAUUUUAAAAUUAAUUUUUGUUCAUAAUGUAGCUCCCCUUUAGCCUUUGAAUACACCUGGCAGCAGUAUGCUUAAAAAUAAGAAGUUAGUUGCCUGGCGCAGUAGCUCACACCUGUAAUCCCAGCACUUUGGGAGGCCGAGGCAGGCAGAUCACCUGACGUCAGGAGUCCAAGACCAGCCUGGCCAACACGGUGAAACCUCGUCUCUAAUAAAAAUACAAACAUUAGCCCGGCAUGGUGGUGCACACCUAUAGUCCCAGCUACUCGGGAGGCUAAGGCAGGAGAAUGGCUUGAACCUGAGAGACGGAGGUUGCAGUGAGCCAAAUAGCGCCAGUGCACUCCAGCCUAGGCGACACAGCGAGACUCCAUCUCAAAAAAAAAAAAAAAAAAAAGAAGAAGUUAGGCUUGUUUUACCUUAUUAACUCCUUUGAACUGUCUGGAUUUCAUGGAAGUUGGUAAGAUGCACUUACAUGGAACAUUGUUCAUGCCAAACAAACUCAUCUUUAUUGUAUCUAUUUGUCACAUAAAUCCUUACAUGGAAUGUUUUGAUUUCUUAAGAAAAAUGAAACAAAGGUUAGCGCCCCUUGUUUUAGACAUACAAACUAAAGCUAGACCCUGUUGCCCAGAUAGUCAUAUUGCUUCUUUGCAAUAUCAAUUCACAGAGGCUGUGAGAUGUGGUUCAAAGAGUGGAGUCGAGAGUCUGGAUGCUAAUCCUGCCUUUGCUGCAAGAACCCUUCUGUUUGUUACCUUGAGGAAGGCAAAUGUCUGUAGGCUUUGCAUAUCUCAUUUGUAAAAUGAGGAAAGGUAGCUGUAAAAUUUUCUAACAUCCGAAUUAUAUAAACUUUAGACAUAGUAUAAAAUAGGAAACUACCAAUGAUUUCUAAAGAUAAUAUAGUUCUUUCAGACCACAAAUAAUACAUAAUAACAUGCAACUAAGAACAACUUGUAAAUGCAAGAAAAAAACAAAUAAUUGGAAAUCAGAAUAUUUCUGGGAAUUCUUCGUAAUAAAGCAAAUUUCAAGCACAAUAAAGUAAUAUUUAUGCAUAUUUACAUAUUUGCACCUCAUCAUAAGGUCACUCUAGUCCUAAACUGAUGUAGUUCAUCUGUUUUACAGCUGAAGUUAAGUAUGUCCCUUAUUUGUGCUUGGCUUAUUUCUUUCUUAAAUAAUACAUUACACAAGUGAACUCUG